AUGGCUCCGACCAACCUCACAUCUGCCCCCGUGUUCCUCCUCCUCGGCCUGGUGGACGGAACAGACGCCCACCCGCUGCUGUUCCUGCUCUGCCUUGGCAUCUAUCUGCUCAACGCCCUGAGCAACCUGAGCAUGGUGGCGCUGGUGAGAUCCGACGGGGCCCUCCGCUCCCCCAUGUAUUACUUCUUGGGUCACCUGAGCCUCGUGGACGUCUGCUUUACCACCGUCACGGUCCCCAGGCUGCUGGCCGGCCUGCUCCACCCGGGCCAGGCCAUAUCCUUCCAGGCGUGCUUUGCCGAGAUGUACUUCUUCGUGGCUCUGGGCAUCACCGAGAGCUACCUCCUGGCGGCCAUGUCCUACGACCGCCCGACGGCGGCGUGCCGGCCCCUGCGCUACGGCGCGCUGGUGACGCCAUGGCGCUGCGCCUCGCUGGUGCGUGCGUCGUGGGCCGUGACGCACCUGCACUCGCUGCUGCACACGCUGCUCCUCUCCGCGCUCUCCUACCCCUACCCCACCCCCGUGCGCCCCUUCUUUUGCGACAUGACGGUGAUGCUGAGCUUGGCGACCUCGGACACGUCCGCCGCGGAGACGGCCAUCUUCUCCGAGGGCCUGGCCGUGGUGUUGGCCCCGCUGCUCCUCGUGUUCCUUUUCCUACGCGCGCAUCCUGGUCGCGGUGCUCGGCUUGCCGGCGGCCGGCGCCGCGCCUUCUCCACCUGCGGGGCCCACCUAGUGGCGGUGGCGGUGGCGCUUUUCUUUGGCUCUGUCCUCUCCGUGUAUUUCCCGCCGUCGUCUGCCUACUCAGCCCGCUACGACCGCCUGGCCAGCGUGGUCUACGCUGUCAUCACGCCGACCUUGAACCCUUUCAUCAACAGCCUUCGCAACAAAGAGGUCAAGGGCGCCCUGAAAAGGGGGCUCAGAUGGAGGGCUGCACCCCAAGAGGCGUGA